AUUCAGUCACAGUCACAGCCACCAUGCCAGGGAGGACCUGGGAGCUGUGCCUGCUACUGCUGCUGGGGCUGGGACUGGGGUCCCAGGAGGCCCUACCCCCACCCUGUGAGAGUGAGAUUUACUGCCACGGGGAGCUCCUAAACCAAGUUCAAAUGGCCAAGCUCUACCAGGAUGACAAGCAGUUUGUGGACAUGCCACUGUCUAUAGCUCCAGAACAAGUCCUGCAGACCUUCACUGAGCUGUCCAGGGACCACAAUCACAGCAUCCCCAGGGAGCAGCUGCAGGCGUUUGUCCACGAACACUUCCAGGCCAAGGGGCAGGAGCUGCAGCCCUGGACCCCUGCAGACUGGAAAGACAGCCCCCAGUUCCUGCAGAAGAUUUCAGAUGCCAAACUGCGUGCCUGGGCAGGGCAGCUGCAUCAGCUCUGGAAGAAGCUGGGGAAGAAGAUGAAGCCAGAGGUUCUCAGCCACCCUGAGCGGUUCUCUCUCAUCUACUCAGAACAUCCCUUCAUUGUGCCUGGCGGUCGCUUUGUUGAGUUCUACUACUGGGACUCCUACUGGGUCAUGGAGGGUCUGCUCCUCUCAGAGAUGGCUGAGACGGUGAAGGGCAUGCUGCAGAACUUCUUGGACCUGGUGAAAACCUAUGGGCAUGUCCCCAAUGGUGGGCGCGUGUACUACCUGCAGCGGAGCCAGCCCCCACUCUUGACCCUCAUGAUGGAUUGCUACUUGACUCACACCAAUGACACCGCCUUUCUACAGGAAAACAUUGAAACACUAGCCUUGGAAUUGGACUUUUGGACCAAGAACAGGACUGUCUCUGUGAGCUUGGAGGGAAAGAACUACCUCCUGAAUCGCUAUUAUGUCCCUUAUGGGGGACCCAGGCCUGAGUCCUACAGCAAAGAUGUGGAGUUGGCUGACACCUUGCCAGAAGGAGACCGGGAGGCUCUGUGGGCUGAGCUCAAGGCUGGGGCUGAGUCUGGCUGGGACUUCUCUUCACGCUGGCUCAUUGGAGGCCCAAACCCCAACUCGCUUAGCGGCAUCCGAACAAGCAAACUGGUGCCUGUUGACCUGAAUGCCUUCCUAUGCCAAGCAGAGGAGCUGAUGAGCAACUUCUAUUCCAGGCUGGGGAACGACUCCCAGGCCACGAAGUACAGAAUCCUGCGGUCGCAGCGCUUGGCCGCCCUGAACACAGUCCUGUGGGAUGAGCAGACCGGAGCCUGGUUCGAUUACGACCUUGAGAAGAAGAAGAAAAACCGGGAGUUUUACCCAUCCAACCUCACUCCACUCUGGGCCGGGUGUUUCUCUGACCCUGGCGUGGCGGACAAGGCUCUGAAAUACCUGGAGGACAACCGGAUCCUGACUUACCAGUAUGGGAUCCCGACCUCUCUCCAGAAGACAGGCCAGCAGUGGGAUUUCCCCAAUGCCUGGGCCCCCCUGCAGGACCUGGUCAUCAGAGGCCUGGCCAAGGCACCUUUACGUCGGGCCCAGGAAGUGGCUUUCCAGCUGGCUCAGAAUUGGAUCCGAACCAAUUUUGAUGUCUACUCGCAGAAGUCAGCCAUGUAUGAGAAGUAUGACGUCAGCAACGGUGGACAGCCCGGUGGGGGAGGAGAAUAUGAAGUUCAGGAGGGAUUUGGCUGGACGAAUGGCGUGGUCCUGAUGCUGCUGGACCGCUAUGGUGACCGGCUGACCUCAGGGGCCAAGCUGGCUUUCCUGGAGCCCCACUGCCUGGCGGCCACCCUUCUGCCCAGCCUCCUGCUCAGCCUCCUGCCAUGGUGACAGCCCUCCUCUCCUCACCUGGCCCCAGCUCCUGCCCCAUUAAACCUCUGCACCAGUUCCUGCCUUCCCCUGCCUCUUCAUGCCCUCCUACCUCCCAGCCUGUCCUCAGAGCGAAGUGGAGGGCAGGGUCACGACCUGGAGGUCAUGGGUAGGGGCCUAGCUCCCUCCUGGAACCUUGAAUAGGGUGGAAAUCCUGCUCUGGAGGGAAGACCUAUCCCCAAGUGCCUCAGCGCCAAGCCCCACACCGGCCUUCCACUCACUUCCGUAGUCCAAAGGCUUUAUUGUUCUGCUGAAAUGCUUACAAAUACUGAAAACCCCCAGCCUGGGCCCAGGCAACCAAGGGCUCAAUGCUGGGAAGGAGAGCAGGGGAGGUGGGCUUAGUGUUAAGGCGUGAAGGGCGAGGCCAGACAGCUGGAGGCCUGGUCCUCCACUCUCCAUUUCCAUCACCCUUCGGAGGCUGAAGGAAGGGCGGCGGCACCACAGGGCCCUUCCCCUCUGCUGCAUCAUCUCCUGCUCAGGCUUUCUCUCUAGGAGCAUUGGAGGAAUCCUCUUUCCCUGUCGGAAACUCAACACUGUACAGAACUCCAACCAUAACCCUUCUAGCUUCCUCUCCCAACUGCAUCGCUCCUCCUCUGUUCCAUAGAUCCCCCGGCUUCAUCCCUUCUGGCUCUAAGCAAGGCACCAGUGGAAGGGAGAGGGCUGGACUGGGGGGCUGGCAGCCUGUGCAUCAGGGCUGAAGACACAGGCAGGGGGAAGGAAAAAGGUAUUCAGUCCCUUCCCCCCAGCAUGAGAUGCCCAGGGGCCUGGGCUGGAGAGAUGAUGGCACGUACCCUCAGAUGGCCCACAGCUGAAGCAGUGGGCUGGGCCACAGAGCUGCAGCAAUUAGUAUGUAACCAUGGCAAUGAAGCAGUCACUAUGGUAACCAUGGUGAUGAGUCUGCAACUAGGGGAUGGAGCUGGGACCUCAAGGUUGA